CGGGGAAGGGGAGGUAUCCAGGUUUUCUGCCUGACUCGAGUCCCCGACGAGCAUCAACCGCAUUUGGGGAACCCAAGACAGCCUCCCCAGCAGCUUGCCCUCGGUUUCGGGGACCCCUGAACAACCCAACCAAGAAGGGAAAACUAGGGCGCACUCUCGGUCGGGGUGGGAGAGGAAAGGGGCUGGGGCUUCACGGAGUUUGGAGUUUGAACCCACCCGCACCCCUUUGAGCUAGGAAGUUUGACCCUUCGACGAGCAGGUCGCCUGGGGUAUGCCCCUGUCUCCGUGCCUCUGUCUCAGCACCGAGCGUCGGAGAGAGAGCGCGCCCUCCGCACCUUCUCCCACUUUGGGACAGACUUUCCCUUGCGCUGUCAGAGGGACCCGAGGCUGAGUACGAGGCGAGGCGGCAGGCAGCUCAGGCUGGCUGCGCAGCGCUGAGUGGCACCGCCGCCGCUCCCCAGGGGCAGGGCCCACCCCACACCCGGCUGACUCUCGCUGCCCUUCCUCCUUCCCUAUCGGGCUCUGCGGUCUGGAGGCUGGAGAGCGGUGAGUGGAGGGGCCUUCCCUGCGAGAAGUCAGAGCUGUGCCCGUGGGCAGGCUGGCUCCGCUGUUCUGCUCCAAGGAUUACAUGUCCUUCAAACGUCCCUGCCCCUUAGCACGAUACAACCGCACCAGCUACUUCUACCCCACAUUCUCAGAGAGCUCGGAGCACAGCCAUCUGCUCGUGUCCCCCGUGCUGGUGGCGAGUGCCGUCAUAGGUGUGGUCAUCAUCCUCUCCUGCAUCACCAUCAUUGUGGGCAGCAUCCGCAGGGACAGGCAGGCCCGGCUUCAGCGGCACCGCCACCGCCACCACCGCCACCACCACCACCAUCAUCACCACCGCCGGCGUCGACACCGAGAGUACGAGCACGGCUACGUGUCGGACGAGCACACAUACAGCCGCUCAAGCCGCAGGAUGCGCUAUGCCUGCAGCUCCUCAGAGGACUGGCCCCCACCCUUGGACAUCAGCUCUGACGGGGACGUGGAUGCCACGGUGCUCAGGGAGCUGUACCCAGAUUCUCCACCAGGCUACGAGGAGUGUGUGGGGCCAGGGGCCACUCAGCUGUAUGUCCCCACGGACGCACCACCACCCUACUCGCUGACUGAUUCCUGCCCCACGCUGGAUGGCACCUCCGACUCAGGCAGCGGCCACAGCCCUGGCCGACACCAGCAGGAGCAGAGGACCCCGGCCCAAGGUGGCCUUCACACGGUCUCCAUGGACACCCUUCCCCCCUACGAGGCUGUGUGCGGGGCUGGCCCCCCAUCAGGCCUGCUGCCACUGCCGGGCCCAGACCCAGGGCCAAGGGGCUCCCAGGGCUCACCCACCCCAACCCGGGCCCCAGCCUCUGGCCCAGAGAGGAUUGUGUGAGGGACCCAGCCAGCCGGGUCCUGCUGGUCCCUACAGGCUGAACCACAUUCUUUAGGCACACAAAGGCGUGCACACACACACAGAGAUGCACACGUGACUCAUAACACACACAUAGACCAAACUUGUAUACACACAGACAUCUACACUGACAUACCCCAUGUACACACACAGAUCUAGACGUGCUCCACAUAUGUGUGAAUAUGCGCACAUACAGGCCUACCACAAACACAAAACCCACCUGCAAAGGUUUCACGGAACGUGGAGCUCUCCUGGCCUCCCGUCCCUCCUCCCGGCCUGUUUGUUGUGCCUCUGUAGAGAGCGCUUCGGAGAGAGAGGCGAAGUAGGAAGUGGGAUUUUCUCUUCCCUCUCCUGGGCCCGUUUGCCCCUACCCUCGCCCAGCAAGCUGCGCCCAAAUUCUAUUCUGCCUCUGGAAACUGCUGGACCAUCCAAGGUCAGCUGCCUGCCCUGACCCCUACCCCAGGGCCAGCUUGUCCUCCUGGGAGGCGGGACAGGCCCCAGUGAGGUUCCGUUGUGCGCUGUGCCUAUCUCUCGAUUCCAGGGCAGAUGAGCCACAACAUCACCACCCUGCCACUUACAAGGUGGGGGACCUGGGUCUGGGGUCUCAGGCGCAAACUGGAGGCCCUCACAGCCCACUAGGCCCCCUCCCAACCCCAGUACCCUCAGUCCCUCAGUCAGGUGGUGCUAGUAGAGCUAUCUCUGACGCUGCAGGCCCCAGGUAGAUGGGCAGGGCCCUCCGUGGGUGUGCAGCGGCGGUUCCCUCAUCAGUCCAGCCACUGCCCAGGACUAAGGGUCUUCAAGGAAGAUGAGGCCAUUGCCCUUCUCCAGGUGGCUUCACCACAGUGCUGCCUGGGCACCUCUCUGAGGCAGAGAAGUGGCCCCUCCCUCAGUCCCUGCCUGGCCGACCACUGUGGCCUGCACGCGAAUGGGUCAGAGCCAGACCCCGGAGCUGGUGCUGUCCUUCUAGGUGGCUGCUCAUAGCUGGGGAUGGUGAGUGGCUGUGUUCUGGCCUUGCCCACGUGGGUGUUUGCAGAGACAAAAUGAAGGGGAUAUGCUCCCCAUAAAUACCACCUUGCCACCACAAGAGGACCAGAAGGCUACUCAGCCUUGCUGCCACAGAAGGGGAUUUGUAGGGUCAGCCUGGCUGCAGAAAGGCUGGCUCAGAUCUUGACCAAGAAACCCCAGCGAUUUCCAUCAAAGACCACGCAGGUAACAGAGGUGAUUCCUGAAGACCCAGCCCACAGAGGGUGGCAGCCAAGCAUCUCUGAGCAGUGUCCCUGCUAGCAUCGCCAGCGGCCAUCACUCUGCCUCCCUCCCACCUCUUGUCCCUCGUCGUUAAAAAACAGCACCCUAUCCUGCUUCCCCACAUUUCUGUUCCUCCAAUGAAGGGCUAAGACUAUUUAGUAAUCUCUUUCUUAAGCAGAGGAGUGGCAAGGAUGGCAAUCUUGAAUUUUAUUUUCUGUAGAGAUAGCAUUUCUUCUGGUGCGGAGCUGAAAGGAAUCCACCCAGAAGUUCUGUAGCAUCCUGCGUGCAGCCUCCUGGAGCCCCAGACUCCAUCUGGGGGAGGGACUUGUUUACAAGCAGUUCUGACCACCUUAGUGGUGUACUGUUUUCUAGGCAAAAAAUAUCUGUCUGUUGUACUGUAUAGCCUUUAAAAUGCAGUCCAGGAAUGAGACUCUUUUAAGAAACACAUCCUGCUUCUGCAAUUCCAGAGAGUGCUGGGGGAAAAAAAGGGAUAAAAAUUCCUACCUACUCAUCAGUGUUUGAAAGAUGGAGCUGAAUAGCUUUUCUUGUUCCUGGACUAGGCAAUGAAUAAGCAACAAUGUAUCUUUUCUGUGUUCAAAAUAAAUACAUAAUAUCAAUAAAAUGUAGCAAGAAGUAACACUUUCA